CAACAGACCAGACUUCAGGGGCAUGCUGCAAAUAUCUAGCAGUUGCUGCUGCAUUUGUGUUGCAGCUGCCCUAGGGCUGAGCCCUUAGUCUCAACUCAGUGGUCUGCAAGCUGCCUGUGUAUUCUUUGGACUGGCUGGAGCCAAGGUAAACCAAGAGGGGGCCCCAGGUCUGCCCUCUGGCUGAGACUCUUGGCUGUUCCUGCAUCCAUACACUCUGCUUAGAAUGUCAUAAAAGGAUUAGAGAAAUCCCUAGGACACUGUUCUGUUCCCAGGGCUGAAAGAGGAUUCCUGGAAUACCAGAGGCCUCAAGGUAUGAUUACAUUUCAAUCCCCAUGCAAAAUUGUAGAAUGUCAUACCAUCCAGUUUCUCUGUCAAUAUUAGUUCUAUUGUUUGCAAUCUGAGAAUGGGAGCCAAUCUAUGGCCUCUCCAGUGCCUGCUUUUGGCAAGAGAGACCAUCAAGAGACUGAAUGACCAGUCACUGCAUGUUUUCUACCUAGAAUGAUAGGAAACUGGUCCCUUGAUGUACUGUCUUCAGGAGGGACAUUGGGCUGGCUGAUCUGAGCUGGAAAUUGAUCUUUUAUCUUUCUGAACUGGCGCAAGUGAAGAGAUGACAGUAGAUGUGUCAGGGAAGCGGGGAGCUGCCAUCCUAAAAGGAGUAGUUCCCUGCAGCCUGGAGAGGCCAGGGUAGAAUAUUUCCCAAGAAAAUCAUGAAGAGGACAGAGAGGAUUGGGGAGGCUUUAUUGUGUUGGUGACGAUCUGUGAAUUAUAAUCAAGGCAUGUUGAUGGACAAGUCCUUAGCAUGUGUUGCCUAACAGUUUAUUCCUUCCACCUAACUUAAUGGAGGCCCACUCUGUGCUCGCCACAAUACAAAGAUGUAUUGCAUUGAUACAAAGACGAAUCAGCUUUAGUGAUUCUCAUGGGAGUUGUACUUAUAGUAGAUUAGCAGGUGCAUGGACAUGAUGUAAGUGGAUGGCGCCUCCUUGCACCCUCCCUUGUUAUGACCACUGUGAGGUCCUUCUCAACUAUGUCUGCAAAAAGUGCCUGCUUUGUCUGUUCUCCUGGGGAACAGAAAUGCUGAUGUUUCACUAGGCGUUGUUCCUAGGUGAGUAUUCUGGAUGGUGGUGGUGGAGCCUAUAAACCAAAACAUGUCUGAAAGAGUUCUCAAUCAAUUUAGAGGUUCAUUUUGCCAAGGUUGAGGAUGAGCCCAGGAAAAAGAGAUAAAGGCUACAGUAGACUCUGUGGCCUGUGCUUUUUCCAAAGAGGGUUUUGAGAACUUCAGUAUUUAAAGGCAGGAGAGUGGGAAGGAGCAAAAAGAGGGACACUCAAUAGUGCAUUCGGCUCCUGCUCAGUAAAUCUUGUAUUUUACAUAAGAUAAAGUAAACAUAGAGUAGAGGAAGAAGAAGUCAGAUCUGCAUUUGUCUUGAGGUGGGCAGAGGGAUGAUUUCUAGUCUUGUCUUUGUCCCUUACCUGUGAAGAUACAUUGUCAGGGUGAGAGAGGCUACCUGGGGAGAUAGGUGACCUUCUCUCUUGCAGCAAUCUGUUUAGGAACAAAGAGAAAGCAGCUUUUGCAUGACAAAGUUCACUCUUUCUUUUGGCAUAGUGAGUUGAGGGUCCCAAGAUUUUACUUUCCUUUCACAAACCAAAUUGUGACAUGGCUGUGAGAGGAUGGUUUCUUGUAUCUUGUAUCUUCUUGAGGAUUAAUCUAAAUCAUUUGUGUAAGAGAAGGAGGUAGACUGGGAAUCAGGACUUCAGCUUCUAUGCAUGGCUCUGACACUCAUCUCUUAGUAGGAUUUUGAACCCUGACUUGCUUAUUGCUUCAGUUCCUCUUGUUCAAUGGAAAGGUUGGGUUGCCUGAUAUAUCAUAUAUAUACAUAUAUGAUAGAUACAUAUUAACAUAUAUAUAAAUCACAAUAUUCUUUGGAACAGGAACUCUGAAAGAUGCAAAUAUAGGAAUAAAGGGGUUUUGUUUGAGAAAGCUUGCAAGAUGUUAGGUCAAACAAAACAAUUAAAUAGUGUUCUUCUUAUUGCAGAACUUUUUAGGGCCUUUAAUAGACUACUAUGGGGAAUUUCCAAAAGAGGGUACAAUAUGCAGUGAUUCUCAAACUUAGUUGACCAUAGAAUACUUGUGUUGGGGAGAAGCUUAUGAAAUUAAUAUUCCUUGGAAUUCUACUUUGGGAAUUGUAAGGGUAGACCAGCGAUGUUCAAAUGGUGGCGAUUUUGCCCUCGAGGGGACGUUUGGCCAUGUUGGGAGACAUUUUAGUUGUCACAAUUAAGGAUGGGGGUGGAAUGGAGGAGAAUAGCUACUGGAUAGAUGCCAGGGAUGCUGCCAAACCUCCUGCAAUAUACAGGACAGCCUCCCACAACAAAAAGUUUAUCCAUCUAGCCAAAGUGACAAUUGUGCUGAGGUUGAGAAACCCUGAACUUAAAACCCCCUUCUGUUCCUGGCUCUAACACUUGGGGGAUUAGGUGGUUUGGUGACCCUUCCGAACUUGGCAUACCAGUUCACCCUCAGGCAUCUUUGGCUCUUGAACUGUAUAUUAUUCUCUAGAAGGCAGGAGAGGUGAGGCCUUUCAUACUCAUCCCUGCAGACCUGCACAUUUCUGGCACCAGACCCAUAUAUCUAUAUAUCUAUAUAUUCAUUUACCACAGCCCAGCAUUCCUGGCAGCCUGAGAGCUGGUGGCUAGUUGAGAAGAACAUUUAGUCUCCCUUUCCUGGGUCUUGUUUCCACCCCUAGUGGCCAAGCUGGGGCAGCUCGCUUUGCUCUGUGGUCUGACAAACUUGGAUUUCAAAACCCACUGCCUGCCAGGAGCAGUUCCCGCAGACAGAGCUCAGAUUCCAAGAAGACUAUCUGGCUCUUAGAGAUCCAUCAUCUUUAUGAAGUUUUAAAAUCACAGAUGGUUUUUAUGGAUAUUCAAGGUAUUCCAGCCUUUCAUGUUUUCUCUUCAUCCCUCUUUCUUCCCCAAUCACACAUUUUUCUCCAGUAACCAAAACACAAUAGGUAAUGGAAAUUCCAUUACAGGCUGACCCACAGAGACUGCAUGGGACCAAUGCAAUUAUGUCUGGAGCAAAGCACUGUCAUGACUAAUUAGCCUCUCACAUAAAUGAAUUUUCCUAUGGAUAACUUCAGAAAAAUCAGCCUGCAAAACACACUCCUUAUUAGUUUUCCUUCCUUCUCUGGGCUUCGGAGUUAGGCUUUCCCUAAGGAUUCUCUCCACCACUGGGCCACGUGAACAGUCUAGCCCAUGGUGGAAAUCCAUUUUCUGCUUGCUCUUCACCCCCUCAGUCCUGUGCUUAGUUUCAUUAGAGACUAAGUCUCAUCAGAGACCUCGUUAUUUUUAGGGUGAUGAGCUAUUUAUUGAGCAACUUGCUUCUCUCUUGGAAGGCAACAUAGGCAGUGAUGAGCAGGGGCUCUGUCACCCCAGCUCUGCACUGACAGUAACUUUGGGGGAACCUUGGAGAAGCCACAUUGGGACCUCCUGGUUUUGUCUUCCCACCUGUAGAGAGGGGCAUUGUCCUUGAUCUAGAGAUAUCAGCUGUGAUUGAAUGAGUGUAAUUCACGGAGCAGACUUUAUUGGCCACUGAAUUUAGAAGGGAUUAUAAAACACAUCUUCCUUCAAAAGGAUGCUUAGAGCUGGGCAUGGUGGCUCACACCUGUAAUCCCAGCACUUUGGGAGGCCGAGGCAGGUGGAUUACAAGGUCAGGAGAUCAAGACCAUCCUGGCCAACAUGGUGAAACCCUGUCUCUACUAAAAAUACAAAAAUUAGCCAGGCGUGGUGGCAUGCACCUGUAGUCCCAGCUACUCGGGAAGCUGAGGCAGGAGAAUUGCUUGAACGUGGGAGGUGGAGGUUGCAGCAGUGAGCCGAGAUCAUGCCACUGCACUCCAGCCUGGGUGACAGAGCGAGACUCCAUCUCAAUAAAUAAAUAAAUAAAUAAAUAAAUAAAUAAAUAAAUAAAUAAAUGAAUGGAUGGAUGCUCAGGAUUGGAUGACUUAUUGGGCAAAAGCCUGGGCCCUUGCUUAAUUGGUUCAGACAUUUGUUGAGUGUUACCUAUGUGCUAGGAAGUACUGCUAUUUCUUCUGAAGGUUGUAGAAUCUCUAAAUAUAGAGACAAAAAGAGAGGGGAGGGAAGGCCCUUGUGAGGUGUUAGCAAAGACCUCCCACCACCACUGACUGGCACUGAUUCAGUAUCUGUAUCUGGGUGCUGUGCCAAGUCAUCUCCACAUCUCAGCUAACACCCUCUGUGGUGCAUAUUGAUAGUGCCCCCUUCCAGGGGAGGGCACUGAAGCUCACAGAGGUUAAGAACCCGUCCAAUAACAUCUGAGUUAGUAACUAGCAGAGGUGAGAUUUGAGCUCAGUUCUAUCAUACUCUAAAGCAAGCCUCUUCACUCUGUGUCUGCUGUGAGCAUUGUUUUGAAUGGGUCCUUGAUUCCCAGCCUGUAUUGACUUUCCACUGCCUGGGUGCUCCAGCCAGGCUCAGGGCUCUGGGGAAUAUAUAAGUGACCAUCUGGGCUGGGACAGCACCAUGAUGCUGAUGUGCACCAGGAAGGGCUGCCUUUGGGAAGAAUUGCUGUGCACUGCACUCAGAAAUUGCAUGUGCUAGAUGUUGGAGCUGAACUCCCCUAAGAGGAAUUUUCUAAGUGGAUUAUGAAAUCAAUUUAGUGAGUUGUAAUCAAUGUUAAAAAAUACAGGAUAUCAAAGUACAUUCCAUGUAAUAGUGUAGGUAUUGUUUCAUGAAUCCUGUGUUGCAAUUACUUGUAUAGUAGGUAUGUGUGGGUCACGAUGUAAAAUGUAUUUCUUACUUUGGGUCCAGGUCACAAGUUGGAAAGCGUGGCCCUGGAAGGAGGUGGGGCAUGCAGCAGUGCUGCAGAGGGAGGUGUGCAGGCUUUGCCCUUUAAGGCUCUGCUGGGGAUGCCUUGAAGAAGGCAGAGGGCACAGCAAGUCCUGGCAAGUGGGUCAGCAAACUCACUCUGACUGGCUCUAUGAAGUGCUGCAGGGGCUUCAGAGAUGUUAUAGGGGAGGCCCCUACCAUUUGUCAAGAAAGUGGGAGAGAGACUAGCUCUGCUCCGCAAGACAAGAGACUAUAAUAGUCAACAUCUACAAGAAUAAUAACAGCAGCACACUGUAUCCAUCUUUAACUAACACGAACUCUAGCGCAGACUGUCUGGAUUUAUAUCCCAGCUCAACCUCUUAUAACUGUGUGACCUCGAGUCGUUCACCUAACCCCUCAUGCCUAUUUUCCUCAUCCGUAAAAUGGGCAUAAUAAUAGUACAUACUACAUAAACUUGUUGUGAGGAUUCAAUGAGUUACUAUUUAGGGAGUGCUCAGAACCAUACCCAGUAGACAGUCAUCAUAUAUACAUGUCUGUUAUAUACAAAAAAAAGUCAUAUAAGCUUUAUAUGAGUGCCCAAUAGAAAGCUUUACCAAGGCAAGACUUGAAGCAGGCCUUGAAGAUUACUCCAUUGGAUCUUCUUCUUUUCAUCUCUGUCAUCAAUAACUGUUUAUUUCAGGGGCCAUAAAUAUGUUCCAGACACUGCAGAGUCCUUCACGUAUGUCCUACAGUCUGGUGAAGUGGGACUCAUAUGCUCAUUUUACAGAUGAGGAAUGAAUAUUUAAAGAGAGUCCAAGCCAGGCCCCGAUUAUUCUGGCUGUGUAGUCUGUACUCUUGAAUCAGACGACACAGUCCCUCUUUGGCCUGCCAUCUGUGUUGUACUGGGGUCUGGAGAUGGUUGGUGUCCUGUUCUGCCCCUUGCUUAGCUUAUCCUCUCUCAGCCUCAGAAACCAAGGCCCUGUGUGGACAGAAAGCACCGCGAUGAACACAGGUGCCUAUUUGAAGUGCUCUGUUGUCCCAGACUGGAGGCCAGCAGACUCCUAAGCAGGAUGUGUCACCUAGCAGAGACCCAUGCAUUUUUAAAUGUCCUCCUGCCUUUGGAGACAGGUCCUGAAAAAAUACCAGAAUCAUUAGGACUCUUAGUCAUCCAGUUCAGCCUUGGGGAGCUGAGUAUCACAGCCCUGUUGUCAGCAGCAGAAGUCCUGCCACCUGGACAAGGCUGGGAAGGCAGCCCACAUUGCCGCACCAGGGAGACCCCAAGACCAAUGCCUCUGGGGUCGAUGUGGGAUGAUUGGUGGUUGACUGAUGGCAAUAAAUGAGGACAAGGAGAAGGCAGGGCCCCUCAGCUGCAUGCCAUGGGCAGGUUUCAACAGAGUGUGGGCUACAUGUCCAGAUCUCACCCAAGCACUGUGGACAAACAUGAAGGAGAAGGCAGGGCUGCUGCCCACAUGGGGAGUCUCAUCUAUUUGGGGAGAUACCAGUGCUCAGAAGCCUAAAUUCAAGUGCUGCAGGAAUCCAGGGAGGGGGCAUUUAGGGAAACUGGGGUGGUUGUGUAAAACUUCCCCCAAAAGAGAAAAUUCAGGUGAGGGUAACCAAGAUUUGGAGUGACUACAAUGUUAAAUAAAUCGGGGCAAUGUGUUUAUAGAUAAUGUGCUCUCCUUCUGCAAGCUGCCACCAGCCUGCCAAUACUUAUAUCCUCAUCCAUCCAUCCAUCCAUCCAUCCAUCCAUCCAUCCAUCCAUCCACUCAUCCAUCCAUCCAUCCAUCCACUCAUCCAUCCACCCAUCCAUCCACCCAUCCAUCCAUUCAUUUAUUCAGCACAUACCUCCCAGGUGCCUGCCCUGGCCCAGGCCCAGUGCUAGGCCCUGUGUAGACAACGAGCACAGUUGCAUGCUGCCUCUCCUUCCUGCUCAUGGUCUAGUGUGGGAGACCAGCAUUGAACAAAUAAAUCAGCAAAUAGCUGUGAAAUUAAAAUCACAGUGAGUCCAACAAAGGAAAUGAAUGGGUUGUGAUGAGAAAGAACAAGGGGGCCCUAAUUUGGACUGAACCAGGCUGAGUGCAUCUGUCAAAAUCAUGCCUAUCCUUUGAGGCUCAGCAGAAAUACCACCACCUUCAUUAAAUCAGUCUGUUCCUGCCAUUUAACAGGUCCUCUGCCAUACUCUCUUCCUCCCUGGUGUCAUAUUCUACCUUGAUUUAGUUUUGGGUACUUGUCUGUUUCCCCUGAGAGAUCUUCAACUCCUGGAAGGAGAGAUUGUAUUUUUUUUUUUGUCUGAGAACCUGUUGUGAGUAAUCCUCUCUCAGAGAUGCCCAGGUGAAUUGUUGAAUGAAUGAAUGAAUGAAUGAAUGAACACAGAUCUUCAUUCCUAGCCCCAGGCUUCCACUAUGGGUAUAUAGCAGUCCCUGUGGUGAGAGCACCAGCUCCAGAAUCAGCUGCUUACUGACUUUGUGACUGUGGGCAGGUGCCUUGACCUCUCUGAGCCUUCAUUUGCCAUAUGGGGGCAGUGCUAUAAAUAGUUGUAAGGAUGGAAAAGAUUAGGGCAUGUGCAUUACUUAGAUUCAUACUUGGCAUAUAAUGCUUUAUAAGUUAGAAGGAAUGUGCUAGACACAUCCAACAACUCUCAGAAUCCUCACAAAUCUGCUGCAAAGCACUUAUAAUUAUUCCUGUAUUAUAGCUCAGAAACCUGAGGUUUCAAAGGAUUAACUAACCUGCUGUAGUUUGCAGAAUAAAUUAGAUUUUAACACAAAGCAAAACAAACCAACAAAACAAGGCCAAUAUGCAAACCUGGGAUUGUCUGACUCCAAAAGCUUGUCUUCCUUGACAGUGUCCCAUUCCUCUGCCAAGCUGAAUUCUCACCUCUGCAGACAGAGGCUGAGAUGUUUGCAUUUUGGAAGCUCACCGCCUGGCCAAAGGCUAACAUAUUGUUCAUGGAUGGACUGGACAUUUGAAAUUACAUGCUGGCCUUGGGAGGGAAGAGAGAAGGAAUGCUUGACUUCCACGGGGUGCCUCUGCCUUACCCAUCUCAAAGAAUCAGACCCCUCUCUCAUUUUUCAAGGGCCUUGGGGUGAGCAUCCUAAAAGUCUCACAGUCUGUUGCAGCAGAAAGCGUGGCUUUGUCCCCCCUAUAAAACAUCUGGAGAUUUUCAAGUUUGUGCAGACCCCAUGUGAGCAGCCAGCCCUGGGUUGGCAUGGAUUGGAGAGGCAGAGAAGGCAUUCACUUGGCUCUGAUUUUUCAUCCUGUGGCCUCAGAGCUUCAGAAUACAGAGUCCCUACCCCUGGUGUCUCCUUCCUCUCCAUCCACCAUGACAAGCUGUGUCCACAUUCUCUUUUUGGCUCUUUCCUAAGGUAUCGGGCACAGGACUAUGUCUGCCCAAGAAUAAAAAUUAUACCCCUUAUAUUUCCAAAAGGAGAGGCAUAUAAUUUAUGACUAAAACUGGGGUACUCUGACUGAAAAUAUCUACUGCUUAGCCGUUUCUAUGUCGAUUAGAGAAGGUGUUUAUAGCUCAGAACUAGAGGAGAAGAAACCAUUUCUUUGUCACUGAGAAACUCCUUGCCAGGGUCUCUCAGUGAGAAACAGGACAUGUGGAGCCCAAGAUAGGGCAAAGCCAAGUCUCCUUAUCUUAUUUAGUGACAUUUUUUUAAGAGUAAAAAAUAAUCACAUGCUUUUUGCCAAAUCCAGCCCUAAGGCAUGGAUCCAACAAAACAUCACAUUAAUUAGAUAAUCUAAUUUCCAAAAACAGACCCCAGCGCAGACACCCACUGUCUAGCAGUGAUGACAAAGGGAACAGACAGCUGACAUCGUGGCUUCCUCCUUCAGAGUUCAUGUGGACACCUACCAAGAAUAAGGCCUUGGCCAGAGCUUUAUCUGUCCUUGGACUAGAAUGUUUCUUAGUGAUGCCAUAACAACGGGGUUGACUUAAAACAAUGUUAAUUUAUUGUCUCACAGUUCAGAAGGCUGGAAGGCUUAAAUCAAGAUGUCAGCAGGGCCAGCCUCCCUCUGAAGCCUGUAGGGUUUCUCCUUCCUUGCAUCUUCCGUGUUUCUGCUGGUGGCUGGCAGUCUUUGACUUGCAGCCACCACUCCAGUCUCUGCUUCUUUGGUCAUGGGGCGUUCUCCCUAUGUGUGUCUCUUUCCUCCUCUCCUAGGGACACCAGUCAUAUUGGAUUAGGAGCUCACCCUACUCCAGUAUGACCUCAUUUUAACUUGAUUACAUCUGCAAAGACCUUCUUUCCAAAUAAGGCUUACCUUCACAGGAACUGGGGAUUACUAUUGAAACAAAUCUUUUGGAAAAAAACACUGCAACCCAUUACAGGUGCCUAAGACUAGAAAGAUGGGUCAGAGCUGCUACUGCCAGUGUGAGAAAGUGGACAAGUUGGAGUUCACCUGGGAAUAAGAUCCUUGGAUGGAGGAGCAAACUCCAGCUAGAGGACCGAAGCCUUGAAAUCAUUUAUUCUGCAGAUCAGUGUUUCUCAAAACGGGGUUCCCCUAGCCAUCAGCAUUAGCGUCAGCUGAGAAACAUGUAAGGCAUGUAAAUUCUUAUGCUCCAACCUAAGCCUACUGAAUUGGAAACUCUGGGCUGGGGUAGUUUCUUAUUUUAAUAAGCCUUCCUGGUGACUCUGAUGCACACUAAAGUUUGAGACCCAUUCCUCUAAAUUCUGCCGUCUCUCCUCACUGCAUCACUUUUCAGUGGGGCUGCCCUUGGACACUGGCAGAUAUUUUGGGUUAAAGAAGAAAGUUAUUUGGUCAAAAUGAGUGUGGGCAGCAUUGUAUUGGUCUAUGUUGAACAGGUUCCUUGACUGAAGGCUAUCUCUGAGCUUUUGCUAUGCUGUAUGCAGUGAGCAUUGAACAUUUGUUAGAAGAGGAAUGAUGGCAUUUCCAGAUUUCACUGCAAAGAGAAGUGUCCCUUUUGUAUGGAGUUUCCCAUCAGACUGGUGUUCCGUGAAUUUACACUGGGAAACAUGGCUCUAGUCCACAUAUCAAGGCAUUCAGUGAAUUUUUAUGAACCGCCUUGUGAGAACAAGACACUGUGCUGGAGAGAUACAUCUGUGAACAAGACGUGGCUUCCGUCUCUAGGAAACUGAUAGUCUAGUGCAGGAGCUGGCACACCACAGGCUGUGGGCCAAGUCUGGCCUGCCAUCUGUUUUUGUAUGGCCCAUUAGCUAAGAAUGGUUUUCACAUUUUUAAAUAGUUGAACAAAAAUUUUAAAUGAAGAAUAUUUCAUGAAACAUGAAAUGGUAUGAAAUUCUGAUUUCAAUGUCUCUAAAUAAAAUUCCGCUGGAAUACAACCACACUCCUUUGUUUAUAUAUUGUCUAAGGCCACUUUUGCCCCCCAGCAACAGAGCUGAAUAGUUGCAACAGAGACCAUAUGCUAAAGCCUAAAAUAUUUCCUAUCUGGCCCUUUACAGAAACAAUUUGCCCACCUCUAGUCUAGUGAAGCAAAGAGGCCCUGAACAAGUACUUGCAAAUGCCUUGAGUGUUAUGAAGGAGCAGUGCAAAGACCACAUGAUUGGAAGGUUUUAUUGACUGAUAGCAAUGGUGGUGGUGGAGUGGAGGUGGAGGGUGAGUUAGGAAAGGCUUCCUGGGGAGAGAUCUUAAAUAUGAGUAGGACAUCUGGAAUAUGACUGUGUGAAGAAGGUUGUUACAGGAAAAGGAAACCUAGGACAUGCAGAUCCCUGAAUUAGAAAAGAGGAGUGCUCAUUGAAGGAAUGCAAGAAUGUCCAGUAUUGCUGUGGAUUAAGGGAGGUGAGGCCAAGAGUAUUUCAGUAUGUGGCCAGAUGCCUGGCAAAGGCCAGAUGUGCCAGAGCAUCUUCGACGGCCAUGCUGAGGGCCUUAACUUUUGCCUAAGAGCAAGGGGGAGUCCCUGAGAAGAGUUUAAGCACAGGCAUGAUGUGACUGAUAGAAACCUUGUGGUAUCUCUCUGGCUUCAGUGUGGAGAAUGAGGGGCAGAACUAAGUGGGAAUUGUACCAUUGCAUGAUACAAUGUAAAUGAUUAUGAAGCUUAGGAGUCAACCAGGGGAGAGAAGCUGAGAUGGAGAGAAGUGGGUAGAUUUGAAAGGUGAAGGUUCUCUGUGAUGCUUGGCCUCCCUCCUGCCAGGCCCUUUGUGUUCUCUGACAACCUAAAGAACCUUCCUUCCUGGUUACUGGGUCUGUGCUCUUGGACCCUGAUAUAUUAAUAAAUAUUGAUUGUUUGUUGCACACCUGCUACAAAUCCACCAGGCCCAGUGCUAGAUGCUAUGAAAUAUAAGAAUUAAUAAGCCCUGGCUCCUGACCUCAGGUUCUUAGCCGGGAGACUGAUGGAUGUAGCCACUGGACUAGAAUGUAAUGAGGACUGAUAAGCAGAGAAACAAGUGAUAUCUGAGGGGACUGAUACCUGAAAGGAAGUAUUGAGCAAACAGCCCUGGAGACGUUAGCUCUACUGAAGAGGUCUGGAGAGGCUUCAUGGCAGAGGCAGCGUUUAGGCUUUCUCUUAAACAAUGUGUAGGAUUUGGGAAGGAGAACAGUGGUCAUUAAUCCAACAUGAGCACAAUGACAGGUCUAUUAACAGCCUCCGGUGGGUGCAGGGGAGGCUAGGGGAGCCAUGUGGCUGGCAUGAGCCAUCAGUGGAGGCUUACAGAGAGCAAAGAGGUGCUCCUGUUUUGGAAACUCAAUCUAGACUCCUGAUUGCUUCAUGUGCCUGACAGUUCAGUGAAGGCUGUGCUGGGACCAUGAGUUACCCUCAGCAGUGGAUCAGCAGGGCAGCAGAAGACCCACUCUUUCACUGAUGGCCAGGGCCCUGCGUACCCCAAUUCACUUCAGGCCCUUCCAAGGCAGGUACAAAUCAUGAAUCACAUUCCCCUCUCUAUGACUUUGUUUAUAGGCAGAGCUCUAAAGCUGGGAUAACAGCAAACUGCAUCAACAAGUUCUCUGGGGCCUCUAGCCCAUUGAUCCUAUGACUUGUUGUGAUUGCCCCUGACCUCUUCACUUUCUUCUUCAGUUUGGUGCUUUGGCCACUGGGACCAAUGACUUCCACUGAAGUUUUCUGGUUCUCAGUCCUGCUUUCCAGGGCUGUGACACAGGGUGAUUUGCAGACUGAUUUCUGUCCUGUGCCAGAAGAUACUUAAUAAAUGCUGGCAAUGACGAUGGGUCCCUGAAGAGCAGUUUGCCCAAUUUAUUUUUUAAAGACUUUAAAAAAAUAGUAUAGACAGAAAAGUCUAUAAAAUGAAAAAUUACAAAAUAGCAAAUUAUUAUAGAAAAUUUGUGUCACUACCACUGAGUUCAAAAAAUAAAAUACUGUCGGUAUCCCCAGAAGCUUCCCUGACCAUCCCUUCUCCUUGGCUGGCGUCUCACCUUUGACGUCUCAAGUUCAAGAAAUCUGAGUAACAACUCUUUCUGCCUAGCUUCUAGUAAGAAAAACAGCUGCAAAAGGAGAAAAACAAAACAAAACAAAACAAAGAGACUUGGGAUUCAGGUAACCACCUGACCUUUCUUCCGGAUCUGCUCCUCCAAAAAAGGUCUCCAUCCCUGUCAGUGCUAAGGGCUGGAUGGUUAGUUGUUAUGGAGACGUGGGGCGUCUUUCCAAGACGCCAGCAAAGUUGAUGCCUGCAGCGCUCUGGCAGGUCCCUCUGCUCUGCAGGGCUCUUCUCUCCUUGCAGUUGGCAGAUCCUUAUAAUAAGAGACUUCUGAGAUGUAAAAGGAACUCUCCCCUCAUGUGACCUUCAUGCCAGUCCCCCUGGUGCCACCCCACCUCAGUGCAGUAGCUGAGCAGUAACAGAGGGACAGCCAGUUUCCCUCUGUCCAGGGGAGAUUGUGGGUCUUCAGGUGAGAGUGUGGCGGCACUAACAACAGCCUAGUCACAAUUCAUUAGUAAACUUGGCAUUCAGGUUACUGACAUUUUUGCAAACUGCACUUUCUAACAAUUACCCUCUGGUUAAAAUCUGUAUUUGUAGAAGGAGGCCAGUCUGAAAAGGAAUGAGGGGAAGAACGACUUCCCCUGGAGAAGUCUGAAUGAGGUGGCCCUCUCUUCUAAAAGAAAGGAGGCCCAGAAGAUUAACAAUGGCUCAAGCCAGGCGGAUGGCACUCUCAAACCAGUGGAUGAAAAAGAGGAGGCAGUGGCCGCCGAGGUCGGCUGGAUGACCUCCGUGAAGGACUGGGCGGGGGUGAUGAUAUCCGCCCAGACACUGACUGGCAGAGUCCUGGUUGUCUUAGUCUUUGCUCUCAGCAUCGGUGCACUUGUAAUAUACUUCAUAGAUUCAUCAAACCCAAUAGAAUCCUGCCAGAAUUUCUACAAAGAUUUCACAUUACAGAUCGACAUGGCUUUCAACGUGUUCUUCCUUCUCUACUUCGGCUUGCGGUUUAUUGCAGCCAACGAUAAAUUGUGGUUCUGGCUGGAAGUGAACUCUGUAGUGGAUUUCUUCACGGUGCCCCCCGUGUUUGUGUCUGUGUACUUAAACAGAAGUUGGCUUGGUUUGAGAUUUUUAAGAGCUCUGAGACUGAUACAGUUUUCAGAAAUUUUGCAGUUUCUGAAUAUUCUUAAAACAAGUAAUUCCAUCAAGCUGGUGAAUCUGCUCUCCAUAUUUAUCAGCACGUGGCUGACUGCAGCCGGGUUCAUCCAUUUGGUGGAGAAUUCAGGGGACCCAUGGGAAAAUUUCCAAAACAACCAGGCUCUCACCUACUGGGAAUGUGUCUAUUUACUCAUGGUCACAAUGUCCACCGUUGGUUAUGGGGAUGUUUAUGCAAAAACCACACUUGGGCGCCUCUUCAUGGUCUUCUUCAUCCUCGGGGGACUGGCCAUGUUUGCCAGCUACGUCCCUGAAAUCAUAGAGUUAAUAGGAAACCGCAAGAAAUACGGGGGCUCCUAUAGUGCGGUUAGUGGAAGAAAGCACAUUGUGGUCUGCGGACACAUCACUCUGGAGAGUGUUUCCAACUUCCUGAAGGACUUUCUGCACAAGGACCGGGAUGACGUCAAUGUGGAGAUCGUUUUUCUUCACAACAUCUCCCCCAACCUGGAGCUUGAAGCUCUGUUCAAACGACAUUUUACUCAGGUGGAAUUUUAUCAGGGUUCCGUCCUCAAUCCACAUGAUCUUGCAAGAGUCAAGAUAGAGUCAGCAGAUGCAUGCCUGAUCCUUGCCAACAAGUACUGCGCUGACCCGGAUGCGGAGGAUGCCUCGAAUAUCAUGAGAGUAAUCUCCAUAAAGAACUACCAUCCGAAGAUAAGAAUCAUCACUCAAAUGCUGCAGUAUCACAACAAGGCCCAUCUGCUAAACAUCCCGAGCUGGAAUUGGAAAGAAGGUGAUGACGCAAUCUGCCUCGCAGAGUUGAAGUUGGGCUUCAUAGCCCAGAGCUGCCUGGCUCAAGGCCUCUCCACCAUGCUUGCCAACCUCUUCUCCAUGAGGUCAUUCAUAAAGAUUGAGGAAGACACAUGGCAGAAAUACUACUUGGAAGGAGUCUCAAAUGAAAUGUACACAGAAUAUCUCUCCAGUGCCUUCGUGGGUCUGUCCUUCCCUACUGUUUGUGAGCUGUGUUUUGUGAAGCUCAAGCUCCUAAUGAUAGCCAUUGAGUACAAGUCUGCCAACCGAGAGAGCCGAAGCCGAAAGCGUAUAUUAAUUAAUCCUGGAAACCAUCUUAAGAUCCAAGAAGGUACUUUAGGAUUUUUCAUCGCAAGUGAUGCCAAAGAAGUUAAAAGGGCAUUUUUUUACUGCAAGGCCUGUCAUGAUGACAUCACAGAUCCCAAAAGAAUAAAAAAAUGUGGCUGCAAACGGCCCAAGAUGUCCAUCUACAAGAGAAUGAGACGGGCAUGUUGUUUUGAUUGCGGACGUUCUGAGCGUGACUGCUCAUGCAUGUCAGGCCGUGUGCGUGGUAACGUGGACACCCUUGAGAGAGCCUUCCCACUUUCUUCUGUCUCUGUUAAUGAUUGCUCCACCAGUUUCCGUGCCUUUGAAGAUGAGCAGCCGUCAACACUAUCACCAAAAAAAAAGCAACGGAAUGGAGGCAUGCGGAACUCACCCAACACCUCGCCUAAGCUGAUGAGGCAUGACCCCUUGUUAAUUCCUGGCAAUGAUCAGAUUGACAACAUGGACUCCAAUGUGAAGAAGUACGACUCUACUGGGAUGUUUCACUGGUGUGCACCCAAGGAGAUAGAGAAAGUCAUCCUGACUCGAAGUGAAGCUGCCAUGACCGUCCUGAGUGGCCAUGUCGUGGUCUGCAUCUUUGGCGACGUCAGCUCAGCCCUGAUCGGCCUCCGGAACCUGGUGAUGCCGCUCCGUGCCAGCAACUUUCAUUACCAUGAGCUCAAGCACAUUGUGUUUGUGGGCUCUAUUGAGUACCUCAAGCGGGAAUGGGAGACGCUUCAUAACUUCCCCAAAGUGUCCAUAUUGCCUGGUACGCCAUUAAGUCGGGCUGAUUUAAGGGCUGUCAACAUCAACCUCUGUGACAUGUGCGUUAUCCUGUCAGCCAAUCAGAAUAAUAUUGAUGAUACUUCGCUGCAGGACAAGGAAUGCAUCUUGGCGUCACUCAACAUCAAAUCUAUGCAGUUUGAUGACAGCAUCGGAGUCUUGCAGGCUAAUUCCCAAGGGUUCACACCUCCAGGAAUGGAUAGAUCCUCUCCAGAUAACAGCCCAGUGCACGGGAUGUUACGUCAACCAUCCAUCACAACUGGGGUCAACAUCCCCAUCAUCACUGAACUAGCUAAACCGGGCAAGUUGCCUUUGGUAUCAGUCAAUCAGGAAAAAAACAGUGGGACGCACAUUCUAAUGAUAACUGAACUGGUGAACGAUACUAAUGUUCAGUUUUUGGACCAAGACGAUGAUGAUGACCCUGAUACAGAACUGUACCUCACGCAGCCCUUUGCCUGUGGGACAGCAUUUGCCGUCAGUGUCCUGGACUCACUCAUGAGCGCGACGUACUUCAAUGACAAUAUCCUCACCCUGAUACGGACCCUGGUGACCGGAGGAGCCACGCCGGAGCUGGAGGCUCUGAUUGCUGAGGAAAACGCCCUUAGAGGUGGCUACAGCACCCCGCAGACACUGGCCAAUAGGGACCGCUGCCGCGUGGCCCAGUUAGCUCUGCUCGAUGGGCCAUUUGCGGACUUAGGGGAUGGUGGUUGUUAUGGUGAUCUGUUCUGCAAAGCUCUGAAAACAUAUAAUAUGCUUUGUUUUGGAAUUUACCGGCUGAGAGAUGCUCACCUCAGCACCCCCAGUCAGUGCACAAAGAGGUAUGUCAUCACCAACCCGCCCUAUGAGUUUGAGCUCGUGCCGACGGACCUGAUCUUCUGCUUAAUGCAGUUUGACCACAAUGCCGGCCAGUCCCGGGCCAGCCUGUCCCAUUCCUCCCACUCGUCGCAGUCCUCCAGCAAGAAGAGCUCCUCUGUUCACUCCAUCCCAUCCACAGCAAACCGACAGAACCGGCCCAAGUCCAGGGAGUCCCGGGACAAACAGAAGUACGUGCAGGAAGAGCGGCUUUGAUAUGUGUAUCCACCGCCACUGUGUGAAACUGUAUCUGCCACUCAUUUCCCCAGUUGGUGUUUCCAACAAAGUAACUUUCCCUGUUUUCCCCUGUAGUCCCCCCCUUUUUUUUUACACAUAUUUGCAUAUGUAUGAUAGUGUGCAUGUGGUUGUCAUUUUUAUUUCACCACCAUAAAACCCUUGAGCACAACAGCAAAUAAGCAGACGGACCAAAAGUUAUUUAUGAUUCUGGGGGAAAAAUAACCCAAAGGCAUGCUCCAGACAUAAAUAGCUCACUGCAGGAACGAGUUCACAGAUUAGAAGGGAGCACUUGUGAUCAACGUCAGUUAGGCAGAGCAAGUUUAUUUAAUGUAAAAGAAAAGUUGAUUCUGAUUUAUCAGGAUUAUCAGGGUGCUUUGGGUUUUGAUUUUGUUGUUGUUGUUGUUUUCCUUUCUUUCUUUUUUUAUACACACAAUAAGUUAGCACAUGUUUAUUUGAAACAAGCAACCAAACAGCAAUGAAAACAUAUUGAUUGUUUCCAGUCUCUGGGCCGAAGUAUUGCGAAGCAUUUGAAAAGCUUUCACGAUUUGUGUAGAUGAUUAUGAAGGACCUGCUUGUUGCAAGAGAACAUCAGUGAUUUUUUUAGUUACUCACCAAGGCCUUUUGUCCCAGAGCCAGUUCCCUCUGGGAGUUCUUAUGAACAUUUCUCACCUUAAUAUGGAGGAGAGAAUAGUAUUCCAAUCAUGGAUGUAUCAAAUUCUAGUCAUUUAGUUUAAGUGAAAAGAGGUUUGAUUGCAUAUUAAAUUGUUAUUCUGUCUCCUUAUGUUGCCAUAUGAAUAGCUAUUUUUUUUCUUUCACUUUUGACAUUUGGGAUGAAAAGCCAUAUGUAUCAUAAAUAUCAGAUGUAAGUCAUUAAAAACUGCCUUCCUGGGACUUUUACAUCUUUUAAAAGGUGAAUUACUUACCUUAUGUACAGAAUAAAUAAUGCUCAGGAAAGAGCAAGUAUUUUUCCAUGCAUUCUCAGGGGAUCUUUUUACUCCCCUUUGUUUGAUUAGUUAGGGCCCCAAUGCCAGGUAGGAGGAAGGGCUGGGGCAAUGGUAGAGUGAGAGGAAGACAAACCCAGCUGCAGAUCAUGCUUUUCUAGGAGCCGACAUGCUAAAUAAAUUAGAAUGUAGGAGGAUCAGCCACAGUUGACUCAACAAAGACAAAAGCCAGCCACCACCUUCAACUGUUGGCACAGCUGUGCGGUGCUGGCUGUCCCAAUGCAGAAAGCUGGUGGGAAGGAAUUCCUCAUCAUCACUUUCUUUAAUGUAGCCAAUUUAGGCAGGGUAAUGACGGCAAUAGAGAGCUGCUCCUUGUCAUUAUGAGACGUGGGAUAAGAAGAGUGCAACAGUGAGCCAAACACAUUUUGGUAUAGUUAUUUUUUUCUUCUUUUGUUUUCUUUCUUUUUUAACACUUAGUAAGCAUGAGAGGAGAGGUAGAAAAAUACCCUUUUUUCAACAUAUAGUUGUCAGAUGCUUUGUGCAUGCAAAUCAUGCUUUAGGCAGUGCGGUAUUUCUUAAAAACUGGCCAAUUCACCAUAACCAAUUUCCCUUAUGGAUGGACUAGGCUGGUAUAUACAUAUUUGAAAAGUUUUACUUCAAAGAAUUCCAUCGAAUAGAAUAGGGGUAAAAGGGAGGAGGAAAACAUGUCACAGCUGUACCAUCUCUAAAAAGGUGUUUUUAUGGUGAAUGUUUUGGAUUUAGAUUUUGGAUCCCCCGUCCCCUCAAGCAUGAUAGUUUUGGAUAUUUGCUUGCUGUGUGAAUUGACAAGCACUUUUACUGACAAAUGGUGAGGCUCAGUCAGAACCUCCACCCUCCCCCACACCAAAGACAGGGGCAGCGUAGUAUUCAAACCAGUAUUGUGGUGGGGAAUAAUUGUAUACAUGUAAAUUAUCAAGCCCUAUGAGUGGAAGAAUUUUUUCAAAUUAUUUUUGUCCCUCUAUAUAUUGAUUUAUAUUAUGUAUAACUAUCUCUUUAUAUAAACUAUAUAUAAUUAUAUAUAUAUAACUAUAUAAUUAUAUAUAUAUAACUAUAUAUAUAACUAUAUAUAUGUAUCCCCUAGUAUUGGAUCAUGAAGAGCUCUUCAUGCAUUCUUUGCAAAGGAGGUUAUAAAGUUACGCCCUCAGAACAUUUAUAACUAUAAGAAUGUGCCAGUUAAAGUGCUCAACAGGAAAUAUGACAGUUUAAAAGCAUUGUAAAACUCACAUAGCUUACUUCUCUCUCUAAAGUGCAACAAGGAUGAAUAGAAUGGGCCAAGGUAUGACAAUUAAUGGUUCUGCAUGACCUAGCCACUGCUGGGGGUUUUCUUCUAUAACGUUGUCCUUGUGAAAACUUUUGUGAAAUUAAAAAAAAAGGAGUUACAAA